GGGCCUGCCGGGAGAGUGUCCACUCCUCAGGAGGCCUGGCUGCUCAGCGGCGCCCCUCUGUGGCGAGACUCGCCCAGGCCCAUGUCCGGCCCAUCUCGCCCCAGCCAGGCUCCCCUGGGCAGCCUCAGGACAGAGAACCCUGAAUUCAGAGGGAGGCUGGAGGUGUGGGGCCUCUAGGCACUUGCAGGGUGGAGCUACCCCACACCCAGGGCUCACCCUCAGACCUACCCAGGCGUCUCCAGCCUCACGCUCCCAGAGGGUUCCGGAGGCGGCGAAAAGUCCAGCGGGUCUCCGAAGCCGGUAGACGGAGCCAUGAAGAAGACGUCGGGCUUCAGGAGGGGGAAGGGCGGGCUGCCCUGGGGCUCGGUCAGCAGCCCCGGGAAGGUGGGCGCGGGCGCCGGGAGUGAGAGUGCGGACCACGCCUCCUCCCAGCCCAGGCGCCACGACCCGGACAAGGGGUUCGACAGGCUCCGCAGAGCUGCCGGCCGACACCGGACAGAGACGAUGCGGCGGAUCCUUUCUCUGCCGAAGAGUGGCGUGGAUGACAGAGACGAGAAGAACAGGCUGUCCAACGAACAGAGUUCUGGUGACUCAUGGCUUUCAAUAGAUGAUGAACUCUUUGAUUCUGGUACCAAGACUACCUUUGAGAAUGUUCCACAGAAAUAUGAUAGUCACUUAACUGGAGCUGAUGAUGGUCAAAGAGGAAAAAUUACAAUAAAGGAACAAGAAGGACCACACUCUCAGUAGCAAGGGUAUAGCUGUGCCUUCAGAGAAAUCUCGAAGAAGAGCCCUUGGAUCACCACUCAAGACAUAACAGGAUCAAGGGAAAGCAUGAUUUUCCCUUUAUUUCUGAGCGUGUCUCUGGCCAGAGGGGAAGGAGAAAGAGAUGAAGAAACAGAAAUCAUCAUUGGAAGAUACUACUGCUAAAUGAAGAGAAGAGAAGUCAUGGGAAUAGUCCAUCAAAAGGCGGCAGAAAGGUCAGAAUCAGGACAACAGAUCUAGAGACUACUUUUGCAAAGGAAGAGGGAUUGUGAGUGGAGGAGGAGGGAGGAAAGAAAGAAGUUGGCUAGUUAAUUUUGGAGUUGAUAAUAGGGAAACUUGAGAGCUGUCACUUCUAGUGACUGCAAUAUAUUGGCACUCAAACAGAAGAUUAGGUGAUUGCUGUUCCAGGAAUUACUGGAAGGAGGGAGUGCUAGAAUGGGGGUAAACCACAGGAACUAAUUUCUUCUCUCUGUAACUAUCAGACAUCAAAGAUGCAUGUUUUGUUGAUAUUGUGUCCGGAAUUGGUGGGUUCUUGGUCUCACUGACUUCAAGAAUGAAGCCACGGACCCUCGCGGUGAGUGCUACAGCUCUUAAGGUGGCAUGUCUGGAGUUUGUUCCUUCUGAUGUUCGGAUGUGUUCGGAGUUUCUUCCUUCUGGUGGGUUCGUGGUCUCGCUGGCUCAGGAGUGAAGCUGCAGACCUUCGCGGUGAGUGUUACAGCUCUUAAGGCAGCACAUCUGGAGUUGUUCGUUCCUCUCGGUGGGCUUGUGGUCUCACUGGUUUCAGGAGUGAAGCUGCAGGUCUUCGUGGUGAGUGUUACAGCUCAUAAAAACAGUGUGGACCCAAAGAGUGAGCAGUAGCAAGAUUUAUUGCAGAGAGUGAAAGAACAAAGCCUCCACAGUGUGGAAGGGGACCCGAGCGGAUUGCCACUGCUGGCUGGGGCAGCCUGCUUUUAUUCUCUUAUCUGGCCCCACCCACAUCCUGCUGAUUGGUAGAGCUGAGUGGCCUGUUUUGACAGGGCGCUGAUUGGUGCUUUUACAAUCCCUGAGCUAGAUACAAAGGUUCUCCACCUCCCCAUCAGAUUAGUUAGAUAGAGAGUUUCAACACACAGGUUCUCCAAGGCCCCACCAGAGCAGCUAGAUACAGAGUGUCGAUUGGUGCAUUCACAAACCUUGAGCUAAACACAGGGUGCUGAUUGGUGUGUUUACAAACCUUGAGCUAGAUACAGAGUGCCGACUGGUGUAUUUACAAUCCCUGAGCUAGACGUAAAGAUUCUCCAAGGCCCCACCAGAGUAGCUAGAUACAGAGUGUCGAUUGGUGCACUCACAAACCCUGAGCUAGACACAGAGUGCUGAUUGGUGUGUUUACAAUCCCUUAGCUGGAUAUAAAGACUCUCCAUGUCCCCACCAGACUCAAGAGCCCAACUGGCUUCACCCAGUGGAUCCUGCACCAGGGCUGCAGGUGGAGCUGCCUGCCAGUCCCGCGCCAUGCGCUGGCACUCCUCAGCCCUUGGGCGGUGGAUGGGACUGGGCGCCGUGGAGCAGGGGGCAGCAUUCGUCGGAGAGGCUCGGGCUGCACAGGAACCCAUGGAGGCGGGGGAAGGCCCAGGCAGGGCGGGCUGCAGUCCAGAGGCCUGCCCCGUGGGAAGGCAGCUAAGGCCCUGCGAGAAAUCGAGCGCAGCGCCAGUGGGCUGGCACUGCUGGGGGACCCAGUACACCCUCCACAGCCGCUGGCCCAGGUGCUAAGCCCCUCACUGCCUGGGGCCGGUAGGGCCCGCCCGCCGCUCUGAGUGCGGGGCCCGCCAAGCCCACGCCCACCCAGAACUCCAGCUGGCCCACAAGCGCCGCGCGCAGCCCCGGUUCCUGCUAGCGCAUCUCCCUCCACACCUCCCUGCAAGCUGAGGGAGCCGGCUCUGGCCUUGGCCAGCCCAGAAGGGGGCUCCCACAGUGCAGCGGCGGGCCGAAGGGCUCCUCAAGUGCCGCCAAAGUGGGAACCCAGGCAGAGGAGGCGCCGAGAGCAAGCGAGGGCUGUGACGACUGCCAGCACGCUGUCACCUCUCAAUAUGAGUUAAUCAACUGAGAUUCUCUUCAGCAAUAUCAUCACUUGAAGCCUAAGGUUGAAAUGAAAGAGUGUGUUUCGAACCAGGCAGUCGGAAUGAAAGAUGUACAAGCAUGCACAUCAGGUAAAAAUUUUUGCAAUACAAAUUUAACUCUGGAAAGAAGCACAUUAAAAAUAGUUUAAAUGC